AGUGCGAGCCGGGGAGAGUCGAACCCGGAGCAGGGUCCCAUCCGAGCGUGGACUGGCGGCAGGAUGUUCAGCUGGAUGGGGCGGCAGGCGGGCGGGCGCGAACGCGCUGGCGGCGCGGACGCGGUGCAGACGGUGACGGGCGGGCUGCGCUCGCUCUACCUGCGCAAGGUGCUGCCGCUGGAGGAGGCGUACCGCUUCCACGAGUUCCACUCGCCUGCGCUGGAGGACGCCGACUUCGAGAACAAGCCCAUGAUCCUGCUGGUGGGCCAGUACAGCACCGGCAAGACCACCUUCAUCAGAUACCUACUGGAGCAGGAUUUCCCAGGCAUGAGGAUUGGUCCGGAGCCCACCACAGACUCCUUCAUCGCCGUGAUGUAUGGAGAGACUGAGGGCAGCACCCCAGGGAAUGCUUUAGUCGUGGACCCCAAAAAGCCGUUUAGAAAGCUCAGUCGCUUUGGAAACGCUUUCCUGAAUCGAUUCAUGUGCUCACAGCUCCCCAAUCAGGUCCUGAAGAGCAUCAGCGUCAUCGACAGCCCCGGCAUCCUUUCUGGGGAGAAGCAGCGCAUCAGCCGAGGCUAUGACUUCUGCCAGGUCCUGCAGUGGUUUGCCGAGAGGGUGGACAGGAUCAUCCUGCUCUUUGACGCUCACAAGCUGGACAUCUCAGAUGAAUUCUCAGAGGCCAUCAAGGCCUUCCGGGGCCAGGACGACAAGAUCCGUGUCGUGCUGAACAAGGCCGACCAAGUGGACACGCAGCAGCUGAUGCGGGUCUACGGGGCCCUCAUGUGGUCCCUAGGCAAGGUCAUCAACACGCCCGAGGUACUGCGCGUCUACAUUGGCUCCUUCUGGGCGCAGCCCCUGCAGAACACGGACAACCGCCGGCUCUUCGAGGCUGAGGCCCAGGACCUCUUUAGAGACAUCCAGAGCCUCCCCCAGAAGGCAGCGGUGCGCAAGCUCAACGACCUCAUCAAGCGAGCGAGGCUGGCCAAGGUGCAUGCCUACAUCAUCAGCUACCUGAAGAAGGAGAUGCCAAGUGUAUUUGGAAAGGAAAACAAGAAGAGAGAGCUUAUCAGCAGGCUACCGGAAAUCUACAUUCAGCUACAGCGAGAAUACCAGAUUUCUGCAGGGGACUUCCCUGAGGUCAAGGCUAUGCAGGAACAGCUUGAGAACUAUGACUUCACCAAAUUCCACUCGCUGAAGCCCAAGCUGAUCGAGGCAGUGGACAACAUGCUGAGCAACAAGAUCUCGCCCCUCAUGAACCUCAUCAGCCAGGAGGAGACGAGCACGCCCACGCAGCUGGUGCAGGGCGGCGCCUUCGAUGGCACCACCGAGGGCCCCUUCAACCAGGGCUACGGGGAGGGUGCCAAGGAGGGCGCCGACGAGGAGGAGUGGGUCGUGGCCAAAGACAAGCCCGUCUACGACGAGCUCUUCUACACUCUGUCGCCCAUCAAUGGCAAGAUAUCAGGUGUCAACGCCAAGAAGGAGAUGGUGACCUCCAAGCUGCCCAACAGCGUCCUGGGCAAGAUCUGGAAGCUGGCCGACUGCGACUGCGACGGCAUGCUUGAUGAGGAGGAGUUCGCGCUGGCCAAGCACCUCAUCAAGAUCAAGCUCGACGGCUACGAGCUGCCCAGCAGCCUGCCCCCCCACCUCGUGCCCCCCUCGCACAGGAAGUCCCUGCCCAAGGCCGACUGAGGGGUGGGCUGCAGAACGGGGUGGGAACUGGGGGACCUGGGCCUCAGGCCUGCUCCACCACUGACUCACCGAAUGACCUUGGGCAAGGCACUGCCCUCUCUGUGCCUUGGUUUCCCCAUCUGUAGAAUGGGGAGGGUGGACACUGGAAACUAGAUGACUUCUUUCACCUCCAAAAUUCCCUUAGUUUCUAUGAAAAUAUUGGGGGUAGGGGGGUGGAUUAGGAGAUUGAAGGGUUGAGAAGAAAGAGAAAUUGUCCAAAGAGUCCUCAGAACCUGCCUGGAGAAAUGCGCAUGGGGGUGGGCCUGGUAAGUCCCAGGAACCACAGGAAGUGAGCUAAGGCUCACCCAGAGCAGCUGGGUCUCCAGGCUGCCUGGGCUUUUUGUCCUCAUGAACAACUCUGGAGCAGCUGUCUGUCCCUCAGAGGGCACCUGGAGGCAGCAAAGAUUAUCUUAUUUAUUUUAUUUUGUUUUCUGCUAUAUUUAGAGUGGCAAAAAAAUAGAGCAGAGGGUUUCUGCUGUCUCCAGACUGUCUACCAAAGAGAAGGCGACAGAUGCCUCCUGGGUUUGGAAGGGGGAUGCACUGUGGAUCUGCCAUCCAUUCUGCAGUCUCCAGCAGAGCAGGCAGUCAGGCCCCAGCGUGCCUCCAUCCCAGUGCCCCGAUGACCAUCUGGUCAGCCCUCCCAACCUCCCUUCCAGGGGGCUUACCAGCAAAGCCAUAUUCGGCUAGGAAUUUGGAAUUCACAACCUUUAUUAACCCCUGGCAAAACUUCCCGUUUGCAUGUCAAAUCACAUUGAAGCCUGAAAAUUAGCUUUUCUUACUGGUUUUUCCAAUAAGUAAUAGCAAAGCCCACUUAUCAUACUUAAACUACAGUAAAGAAAAGAGGUGGUUCUCUGCAGUGAUCGUUUAGUGUGGCCCUCAAACAUUAAAUAUCCCGAGGUCUCCUUGGUGGGUGGCAGGAUUUAAAUUCAAUCAAAUCCUGUCCUAGUGUGUGCAGUGUCUUCGGCCCUGUGGACACAGGUGAAUGAGGGACCAGCCCUGCCCUGGGCUGUUGAGAAGAGAUCAGUCCACCCAGAGUUAGACAUUGUUUUUGUAGAAAACAGGCAUUUAUUAUGUCUAGGGUUUUGUGUUUUUUUUUUUUCCUUACAGGAUAAAAGCCUUUAUACAGAAACAAAAUGGAACCUUUCAUAUAAAACCUUUUCUUUAAAGGCUGUGUGGUUCGUAUCAUGAAUGCCCAUCACGAGGCAGGAUUCGGGCACAUACCUGUACUUCUGCUCCAGAGUGUGCGCUCCCCAAAUCCCCUGAGUAAACCUCUCUGGACUGCUGCUCAGACACCUGCGUCAGGUGGAGGUGCCUCCCCCUCUGUGGGCACCAGCUUGGGGAGGUAGGUGACUUUUCCUUGCAAAUCUCCCUGCCUCAUCUCCAGAAAAUUGCAUACCUGCAUGGCCUCUCUGCAUUAUUUAUGCAGGAAGAGACACGAAACAGCAAUGGCCACAUGGUAUGGGGGCCUGCUGGCACCAGAAGUGAAUGAAAUCAGAACCGUCCCACUGAGUCUUCCAAAAGGCACAUAAUUUUUUUUUUCUGUCACCUGCCUUUGGUGACAGGGUCAAAGGCACAGAUUGAAGAGAAAAUCUUGAUUUGGGAGAAGCAUUUAUAUCCAGAUGCCUACCCUUACACUCCCUAGCUUACUUUCUACAUAAUUUAGUUUUAAGAGCAGGAAAUGCAUAACAUGGUUUUUAGUCUUAACAAGCACUUAAAUUCAUUAGACGCAUAGAAAAGAACCAUUUAUUAUUUUAUUAUUUUUAUUUUUAUUUUGAGAGGAAGUCUCUGUCACCCAGGCUGGAGUGCAGUGGCGCAAUCUCAGUUCACUGCAACCUCCGCCUCCCAGGUUCAAGUGAUUCCCCUGCCUCAGCCUCCCAAGUAGCUGGGACUACAGGCACCCGCCACCACGCCCGGCUAAUUUUUGUAUUUUAGUAGAGAUGGGGUUUUACCAUGUUGGUCAAUAUGGUCUCGAUCUCCUGACCUCGUGAUCUACCCACCUCGGCCUCCCAAAGUGCUGUAACCUAAGCAGACAGUUCUGUGAAUGCGUGAGGACCACCUGAAGUCUGCAGCCACGGUGGAGGUCACCAAAGGGUGAACUGAGAGAGAAGAGGGAAUUCACUUGCCCAAAGGUUUACAGAUGCCCAGGCAAACUGAUUUUUCCAUCCAGAAUUAUCUUGUUCUUUAACUCUCCUCAAUUGUCAUAUAUAAACAUGAAUUUAUAUACAUGUGUGUCACAUGAGUAUGUCGUUUUAAAACAACGUGUACAUAUGUAAGUUUUGUCUGGAUACAGAAAGCUGCUUUAGAGGGCAGCAGGUUGAGGUCUCUGAUUUCUCCGUGGAGGAAAACCUCUCAGGCACUGUGAUCUCCCUACCUCUGCGCUCUCAGGUGGGAGAGGCGUCAGGCAGCGGAGUCCUUUCCCUGCUGGCACCUGGUAAUGUUCUUGGAGAGAAAGGAAAAAAAAAGGAAAUCAUUUGGCCACUUUUCUUAAUAUCCUCUUACAUGCAGUCAUUCAUCAAGAAAAGUUGACUGGAAAAGAAAACACUAGAAAAUAUGAGGGAUGGCGACCAAGUGAGGACUUGUAUCUUCCCAGGACCAGUACAAAGUUCUGUGAAUGUGUCCACACCACCAGCUGUCUCCCUACCCCACACGGCAGGGCGGCAGGGCCGACCCUGGGGCCUGCUCACCAUCACCGUUGCCCUUCCUGCACCACCCCAAUUUUCAAAGAACCUCUUCCACAGAGUGUUUAUGUAUAGGAGAGAGGGUGGAAGUACCUAAACUCUAGAACUACAACAUCUAAGAAGCUGAGGCCCUGUUUUCUACACAGCAUAUGGUAUCGCAUAACACAAACCUUCCGGUCUUGAGUUUAAAGGGAAAAUGAAAACUCCAGCCUAUUGCUCCCACAGUCUGCUUCCAAGUUGUCAGCCUGCCAGUGAGGGUCUCCUGACCCCGUUUGUAGAGAAACACUGCACUAAGACUUGGGAAUCUCCCCAGCUCCCAGGGAGGGGUGGCACACAACAGCCUUCCAACCUGCUUCCGCCUCCUGCUCCAGCCCUGCAGCGUCUGUCAAUUCAUUUCUCAACUCACCGCACUUGGAUGGCCUGGGGGCAGGGUUGCUCUUCUGGGGGAGGGUCAUUCAUUCAGUUGGCUUUUGGCUUUCCUUUCUCCGGGCUGGGCCUGGUUCUCUUUUGAACACUUGUCGUGCUGCAGCAAGAGCAUCUUUGGAUUUGGGGCUGUGGAGCUGUGGUUCACCCGCGGGAGUCACAGCCGCGGCCUGGACCUUUCCACCUCGCACCCUCGCUCACCCUCCUUCAUGAUGCCUGGAGGAUGCCUGAGACAAUUGCCUUGAAGAUGAGGAAAGUGUUUCACUGUUUAUUUUCUCCAUGGGAUGUAGCAGGCAAGCAUGCUUAGGACAGAAAACCACUGAGUUUACUCAGGUAAAUGCGGGCCUAAUACAAGAGUAUUGGGUUCCAAUGUUGGUUAACCAAUGCAGUUAAUACGCAAUGCUUCUAUUUUUUUUCUUUUUGUAAUCUUAUUUAGAAGUUUCAAACAAAAAGACAUAGUCUGCUGAUCAAUAAACAUGGAGCUGCCCUCUCCCACUGGCUCAUUUUCCAGUGGCUGCGUGCUGGCCUCUCGGAGCAGAGUGUGGAUCCCUGGAUCCAGGUUGAACCGGGGGAGAAGAGUUAGGGAGAGGGUGUGCCUGUGAGCCCCAACUCUUCCUGUGGAGAGAAACCCAAAAUGCAGCCGCUUCAGAAGGAAAGCGGCCCCAUCAGGUGGGGACAGAAGAGGGUAGGCAGCAGAGGCCAGGUCUGUGGACAAAAGCCCCACUUCAGAGUGGUUGGAAGCCAGGACAGGAGGGACUCAUGGAGGUGACCGCUUCACAGGAGUCCUUUCUCCAGUCGUGCUAGGGAGGAGCCCCUGCCUGUCCAGCACUGCCCCUGCCUCUUGCUGUACCUUGCCAGUGUGCCCUCCCCCCGCCCACUACCAUAGUAGGCAUCUGGCUUUUCCCACCAACCCAUCUACCUUUUUGGUGGUCCAGACCUACAGUCUCCUUGCAGAGCACUCCUCCUCCCACCCUCACUUCAAGUGAGGUUUGGAUGAGAUUGACCACAUCCCCUUGGUCACAAAUAUUGGCUCAGGAAUGGACAUGUGGCCCUGUUCAAGCCUAUGAGAGCCAGGACCCCCAGACUUAUGUUAGAACUCUUGAGAGAGAUACUCUGUCUUCUCUGAACCUUGCAGUAUAUAGAAAUGAGCCUAUUGAUGCAACAAUAUAAAUGGCACUGAGAGGGGUGUCCAGAGCUGCUGGGGUCAGGGGAGGGAGGUCAGCCUGGCAGAAGCCAUCUUGUGGAGCAUGAAAAUGAAAGAGACCUUGAGAAAGGCCAGAGGAAUCCAGGCCUGUGGUGACAACAUUUGAGCUGCUGGAUCAAACCUCACCUGAAGUCCUUCCUAUUCCUACUAGAUAUUUUUUUCCACUGUGUGGGCCAAUGCAUUCCCUUUAUACUGUGUAAGCCAGGCAUGGUGGCUCACACCUAUAAUCCCAGCAAUGCAGGAGGCUGAAGUGGGAAGAUCGUUGAGGCCAGGAGUUCAAGACCAGCCUGGGCAACCUAAGAAGACCCUGUCUCUAAAAAAGAAUUAAAUAUAAAUAAAUAAAUAAUAAAAAUAUAAUGUUUAAACCA